ACAGCGUCUCCAGGUCUGCACCAGGCCCCAGCUGCUCCUCUGUCUGGAAUGAGCAAGACGAUUUUGUUGCUGAGAUGCACGGAGCCCCCCGGCUGACCUUUCCCUGUGCCAGUGAGUACCUGUGGCAUGCAAGGGAGAAAGCCUAUCAGGACCACAGGAGAAAGGUCCAGAGCGCCCAGCCGCUGGUAGACACCCGCGCCCCGCUGACGUUCCGCCAUCUCCACCUGAAACUCAAGAGGCUGAAGCUGGAGGAGGAACGGCUCUCCGUCAUCGAGAGGGACAACCGCCUGCUCCUGGAGAAGGUGGCCUCUGUCAUGAGGACCAGGGGACAGACUGACAGCAAAAACAACUCCAAGCACAGGAGGUUCAUGGAUGCCUGAAUUCUAUCCAUGGUUUUCUGGACUAUGUGCCAAAUCUCCCAGCCCAUGUCUCUAGGAUUUGGCUCUGGCUGGGACGACUUUGGGAACCUUGCUAUGUGUCCAGUUUUCUAUACAGAAGCCUGGACAAGAACCCCUUCCUUUGGGCUGCCAGAAACCACAAGAUGCGAGUUCUCCCUGCCGCCUCCAAUAUGAAUAAGCAGGUCCACAACCAAAGACAGCCUCAUCCCUCAGAGAAUUAAAUAGGACCCCUUUGGUUUUUGGAUAUAGAAGGUGAUUUUUAAAGCCUGGAGGAGAAUUUGGCUAAAUGAAAAUUUAGGGAGGAAGGAAGACAAAUGAAGCCAGCUACCGAUUACUCAUGAAAAGAAAAGAGAAGAAAGCAAGCAAGGAUAAUCCACAAAGAAUGGAUAAUAGAGAAACAUUCCCUUUCUGCUGCCGUGAGGACCACAGUGAAACAGGAGCUCGCUUGCCACUGCCAUCUGGGCACCAUCCCGCUGUCCGCAUCCAACACAGCUAAUUUGCUCCAGUGAAACUUCAAGUAGCCAAAGUCAUCAUUUAAGCACAGUAAAAGAAAGAGAAGACUUAAUUGGAUGACAUCAAUUUGCACAAUAACACGAGUAGGUGGUCUCAUAGAAGACCAGAUAAUAAAGUGAACAGGUCUGCCUGGAAUAAUAACAAAGGUGUCAGUUAAAACGAUGUCUCAAGUACAACACCUUUCUCCUCCGUGUCUCAGGGGCCCUUCCUGGUAUGUGAAAAGAAAUCUAGAGUGUUCGUGUAGGCCUAGCUCUUACUCAGCUUUCAGCCUUCACCUAAAUGUCACAUGGAGAGGAAGGUCCUGAUGGUCUAGAGGAAGGAAGGUCUAGAGGAAGGUCCUGAUGCCCACCAGUGUGGCGCUCAUUCUGUGCUCGUUCUGGCUCCACCGUUGUGUCUUCCUUUACCACGGGCACCACAGUUGUCAUCCAAGCAGCCAAAGUCAUCAUUUAAGCACGGUAAAAGAAAGCACAGUCACUUACUUGUGUGUUGACCUGUCUACUGUCUGUCUUCCCACUGAAUCUCAAGCCUUAUGAUUCCAGGGACUUUGUCUCUUUUGUUUAUCAUUGUAGACUCAAUGCCCAGGCCAAUGCUCGGCACAUAGUAGGUACUCAGUAAAUAUUUGUUGAAUGACUGAACAAUCAAAUGAGGUCACCAGUGACUUCCCAGUUGCUCAAUUUAUUGAAUUGUUUCCUUUUAAAGUUUAAAAAAUAAUGUUUUUAUUGUUCCUGAUUAUAACAUAAUACAUAUUUAUGGAUACCAAGAAGAAAUUUAACUAUCAUUUCAUCACCCAGAGAGAAUACUUUUUGUAUAUUUUCUGCAUUUUGUAUAUUUUUGUAUAUUUUCUGCAUUUCCAAAUAUAUAAUAGAGUUAUAUUUUUGUGCACAUAUAUGUAUUAAGUAUAAUUAAAAUUGUACCUUAUAUGUGAUCUUA